AGAGCUGGGUUACUACAAGUGUGAACCGGCAGCCUGUCUGUUGCCACAGAAGAACUUGGUCACCACACUGAGAAGCCGUGUUUUCUCACCUCCCUGUUACUGUUGUAGCUGUAUCUGGCUUCUCUAGCAUUUUAAAGGAAUUUCUGAUUGAGGCGCUAACAGCUAAUUCCACAGGAGUUGUAAGGCAGCCUGUGCAUAAACUGAGACAGAAGUUUCUCCUCAGAGACUCUCUUUUUAUUAUUAUUAUUAUUAUUAUUGGCAAAGACUUCUGGCUCUCCUCAGAGGAAUACCUUGUUGCUUAAGAUGAGUGGCUGUAGAAAGCGGUGUAAACGUGAAAUACUGAAAUUUGCCCAGUACCUUCUCAGACUAUUAACAGGUUCUCUUCAUACAUUUGAUCACAAUGGAGUUGUGAGUGUCUAGGAUUGCUAAUUUUCCUAAUUUCAGCUAAGGUCU